AUUUCUUUCUGUCCAUCCAUUCAUUCAUCUAUCCAUCUCUCCCUGGAUGGUGUACUAUAGGAUUAAGGUAGCUUAGAUCACAAGUGUUUAAACAAUUGUAGAACUCAUAGCAGGCAAAACUGAAUGUCAUUUUGUAGAGUUCUGUCUUGUUUUCUGUUUUGGGUAUGUUUGUGGUCUUGGUUGCAGAAAUCCAGUCACCAUUUCAUUUCGUUAAGUGGAUUAUAACUUUUUAAGCAAAAUUCUGCUUUGGUAGAUAAUAAAAACUGCAAGAAAACAUUUGAGUAAUAUUAAAUCUAGUACUCUGGUUUAACCCCUGCAAACAGGAGUUCUUGAUUAUUUAUUCCUCACCACAUUUUCUCUGGAUUUAUCUGUUGCCCACCAAAACUGAAGACCCAUUCUGGUGGCAGGUUGACUGUUCCAGAAAGAAUGAAAAAUCUUGUCAUGUGAAUUUUACUUUUGAACUUUUUUGGUUUAGAUCUGCCUUACCUUCCCCCCCCCCCCCCCCCCCGCCCCACACAGCCUUUCCUGUGUGUGUGGAUUGGUGUGCUGUAGAUCUGAAGCUCUCAGAUCUGAGCACGAAUGACAGUCAUCUGGGGAGCUUAUUAAACAUGCAAGAGCUUUAAUCCCACUCCUAGGGAUUCUGAUUCUCCAGGUAUGCAGUUGGCUCAGGAGUUUGCAUUUUAAAAAACACACUAGUAAUUCUGGUGUGCAUGCUAUAGGUAACCCUGUAGUAAGAGGUUCAAAGAACAUAUGAUGUUUCAUUGAAUCUAUGACGCCACAGAUGGUAAGGGUCAGAAUCUGGUAGCUUUCAGCUGCAUGACUCCUAAGCCCUAAUUUCCAAUCUUGUGGCUAAUUUGUUAGUCCUACAAAGGCAGUCUAGUCCCCAGGCAAGAAGGAGGUUUGUUUUGGGAAAGGGCUGUUACCAUCUUUGUUUUAAACUAUAAACUAAGUUCCUCCCAAAGUUAUGGCCUAUGCCCAGGAAUGAACAAGGACAACCUGGAGGUUAGAAGCAAGAUGGAGUUGGUUAGGUCAGAUCUUUUUCACCAUUUCAGUUAUAAUUUUGCAAUGGUGGUUUCACUACUAAGAAAUAAAAAUGUGGUUGUAAGCCUUAUCCUGAGUUUAGUUAAAAUGAGGGAAGCAAGAUGCAAAAUGAGUUUAGUUAAAAUAAAUAGGGUAUUAAGUGCCUGGCAACCAGAGGUUCCUCUUAUUAUCUUAACAGGUUAUUAUGAAGCAUAGCAGAUAUGAGAUUUUAAAAAAUUACAAAGCAACAGUUCUUCAGAUCUUUUACCAUAUAAAUUAUUUGAUUGCAAUGAGGAGUUUAUAUAAGGUGUCCUUAGUUGACAUCUAUUUGUAAUGAAAAUUGUACUGAUGACUUUGUUUUAAAAUGCAACUUAGGUGUAUAUGGGGGUGUAAUAGACUCCAGUUUGGCCCCAUAUUAAUUUCAUCCUACUCAUUUCCAGUCAUUUAGAUGUUGCUGGCUCAGUUCAGAAGUCUGAUUUCUAUCCUCCUUGUACUUCAGUGAUUCCUGUUUUGUAAUUAUAGUCCACUGAAAUAGUAAGGUGUGGCAUAAUCAUUUGAUGUCUACCUUUUUUUUUUUUUGCCACUUUCCUGUUAGAGAGUCCACAGCCCUCAUUAAUGCCAGCUAGGUGAUUAUACACAUAUAUACCAGCCGCAUAGCAUCUUGUACUGAGUAGUGGUAGGAUGUAAUGGCAAUAUUUGGGGUAAACACCAAAUCUGUGUCAGUGUAAACCUGAACUCUGGCUGCCAACUCAGAAAUGCUGUAGUGGCAUAUUGGGUACUGAAUGAGGGCUUAUCUGUAGGUUAGAACAAAUCUUUCCCCAUUAAUGAGAAUUCAGUGAAGAGCAACCCCACCUGCUUAAGGUGCUUCCUUCAGUAGUAGUAGCUUGGAAAACAAAAUAUCUUUUUUAGGAAAAAGUUGCCUAGCCAUGUUAUAUUUGGGUAUAGAGGAGCAGAAGAGCUCAGAUCCAUUUAGUUUUUAGCUCCUUGAAGUGUUUUUGGAAGACAUGGUUAAAUACUUGUUGAUCCACUAAAUACCAGAUUUCUGAAAAGAAUAACUGUAGGUCUCUUUAGCUAAUUCACAUUGAUUUAAGGGGGUUGUACUAUGAAAUUCUUAACAUUGAGAUGAAUCAUGUUGGAAUACUUAUGUUCUCAGAAUGUAGUGUGUAUGGCCUGUCAGGCUUGGCUGCCUCUCCCUACACUAAGUCUUUGGGUAAAAGUUGGCCUAGAUGGGGCACUUUCAUGAUUUAGCUGAGCACUUUUGCUAACCUGUUUUUAAGUGGAGGGAGAAGCAGGUAUUAUAUUUUACCAAUUUCAUUCUUAGAAGAAUGGAGUUUUAUCUAAAUUGCUGUAGAUAGAAGUUUUCCGAAGUGUUUUUCUCCAUUCACUGUCAGGAGCGCCAAAUGAAAAACAAGGUAGAGCAGUUUAUGGUGGAUUGUGGAGGAAAGCUGAACUUGCCUAGUAUAAUCCCAAUUUGCUUCAUAUCUGGCAUUGGUUAACAUUCUAGGGGAAAUUUAAAAACACUUUCUGGCUCAUUUGUGCUUUUCCAUAGUAUACUUCUAAUUCUAUUUCUGUUUCUUAGCCACAUUUAGAUGUUCUCUUUUAAAUGUAAUUUCAAUAUGAUGCUACUUAAGAAAAUAAGAAAAGCCAGAUGAUGUUGAUUCAGAAAACUGUCAAAAAUCUAGGCAUAGAUCAUCUGUAUUCUUUUCCCAAGAUUUUCAAUAGAACAUUAAACAUUUAUUUUAAAACUCUUAUUGGUUCACUUGACCCAUUGUUUAUAAGUUUUUGGUCUGUUGCUUUUUGGGGGACACUUUGCAGAAGGAGUGGAUACAUUUACAUCAUAAUCAUUGGUGAUCUUUUGAAAAAUUUGUCAUUCCUAGUAUUAUAGAAUUCAUAUGGAUCACCUCUCCCCACACCCCCAAUUUUGUUUUUGUUCCUUUUUUUCCCUUUUCAAAAUGUGAGUUUAGCUUGAUUCUUUAAAAAUCUGGGAUACUUUUCUAGUUGCUGGUAGUCAUGUAAAAAUCUCCCUUUAUUUGUGAUCAAGUCAUACCCACCUCUGAAGCUGUACAACAGGAGUGUGUGAGUGUGUGUGUGUGUGUGUGUGUGUGUUAAAAUGGUGGUUUCUUUUAAAAGAGUGUACCUUCUAGGAUUCGGUAUCCUGCUAGUAUUAAAUACUUUCUCAAGUUAGUAACUAGAUUUUUCUUUCAAGCCUUUAGUGUUAAAAACACCAAAUUUUGUUAAAUUUACAAUAUUUCUAACACAAUGAUAGCAGCUCAGAUAUCCUACUGAGUUUUUAAAUGUUAAUAUUUUUUCAAAUGAAUGCAGUCAUCUUAUUCCUUUCCAUUUUGUUAUUUCAAAAAUGUAGCCAGCUUUGCAAAGAUGUGUGUAUAGUUGCAUUCAGGGGAGACAGGGUACUUGACAGCCGUCUGCAUGUGCAAUAGUAAUAACUUGUUAUUAAAGACAAGGUUUUUUAAAGCUAAAUAUUUGGAAUUUUAGAAGUUUGUUAAGCAUUAGAUGCACAUUUACUUCACUCUUUUUUUAAACCUAUCAUAAAAAUAAUCCCAUAUAAACACCCACAUAAAGGAAAUAGUAAUGUAAGUUUUUUCCCAAGAACAUAAUUUUUAUAGUUACUGAAGUGUAAUAUAGUGAGAUUAAUUUUUAUUGGUUUCUUUACAUUUCCUGGGAUUGGUUUGGAAACAUAACAGCAUCUAGAUUUGUUUCCACCUUUGCUAUAGAUGGAUAGCUUCAUCUACAGGAUGGGAAGGACUUUUUUCUUCCUUUUGAAGAGGAUCCAUUCUGUUGUUUCUCAUGGAAUUAUGCUUCUUUCUGUGGAGAGCAGAUUAUGAAAAUGUUUGAUGAACACGUGUGGAGCACAGAAAUUAGGAUUGUUUCAUCUGUCCUACAUCUGUAGUAGUACUUCUAAGAGGACCUGUCAAAGCCAUGUGGAAGUUGUAUGUCCUACACGUAGCCCAGCAAAAAAAGUUGGACUGUUAGAGCCUGGUUGGGAAAGAUGUUUAUUCCUUUAUUUUUAAAUUUUAUAUUUUUAUUUCUUUUUAUUAGGGGUUGACAAAGUACAACCCCUAGGCCUGUAUGGCCCACAAGCCAAAACUGGUUUUCACAUUUUUAAGUGGGUUGAAAAAAAAUCAAAAGAAUAAUUUUGUGACACAUGAACAUUUUAUGAAAUUUAAAUUUCAGUGUCUAUAAAGAAAGCUUUAUUAGAAUAUAAUUAGACUCAUUCGUUCACAUGUUGGCUAUGGUUGCUUUCUAGCUACAACUGCAGAGUGGCGUAAUUGCAGUAGAGAUUGUAUGGUCCAUAAAGCCUAAAAAUAUUUACCAUCUGGCCCUUUUAUAGAAAGAGUUUGCCAACAGUUGCCCUGUUUUACUCACAUAAAAGUAGUUAUUUAUAGCAAACACAGUAUUUUUUAAAAAAUACCAUGCUUUUGUUUGUAAAUGCAACAUCGGAGUAACCUACCCUAGUGACUCUUUGAGUUGUAGCAUUCUUUUGAUUUUAGUAUUAUCUCAUUUUUCUCUUUUACUUUAAAUGCUCUGGGGAUAAAAAUUUAAUUUUUUACAUUCUGUUCUUGAGGGGGUCUGUAUUAGUCUGAGUUCUAUAGAAAAACAGAACCAAUUACAUAUAUAUAUAUAUAUAUAUGUGUGCGUGUGUGUGUGUAUGUAUAGAUAUAGCUCUAGAUAUAUAGACAUAUAUUCCUUAUAAUACAUGUGGAGAUAGCUUCAUUUAUAUACAGGUAUAUGAUUUGUAUGUGCGUGUUUGUGUGUGUGUGUGUAUAUGUUUAUUAUAAGGGAUUGGCUCAUGAGAUUAUGAAUGCUGAGAAGUCCAAGAUCUGACAAGUUGGCAAGCUCUGACAGUCCAGGAGAAUGAAUGGUAUAGUCUGGUCUGAGUCUGAAGGCAUUGUCUCAGUUUAAAGAUAGGCAAAGAAGGCGAAUUCUCCCUUACUUAUUAGAAUCCCUUAUUAUUAGAAUCAUGGGAACUUUCUAAGUUGGUUGGGUUAAAAUUGUCAUUUGUCCAGCACUGAGUUGAAGUAGGAUUGAAUUGAAUGAUAGUUUCUCUAUUUGUAGAGGAUAACUUGUGGUAUUUUCCUGUGGUUUAAUUAAGUGCUGUUUGUUAAUAUUAAGUAGGUACAUCAAAGGGUGUAUUUGUACGUUUAAUUUUCUUGUAUCAUUUCCAUUUCAAGGAGGGGUUCCAAUACCCAAGCUUAGUCAUUUUGCCAUACUGUUGAAUUGCUGGAGUGGGUAGUUUGUAGCAAUUCCCAAAGCAGUUUGCAAAAGCCAAGUUGAUUGGCAUGACAUUUUGUCAACAAGCCUCUUAUAUUAGAGUGUGUCAGUGAACAGCUGGAGUGAAAAGGAAGUGGAUUUGUUUGUAGCGUGAGCUUCUUACUUACCCUUCAUGUGACCCUAGAGAAAUCCCCUGAUCUCAUAUAUGCUGCUGUUUUAAUGCCCCCAGCAACUAGAGGCUGGUGGGAAGAUUACAUAAAAUAAGGGUGUGUGUGAAUUGCACUGACAUAAGUAUGUAUUCAUACUUGGUUUAUGUUAACUGGCAAGAAAUCCCCCUCCUGGUAAAUAAUUUUUUAUGACAAUUUUGUCAAUAUAGAGUGAUGUUUCUGUGGUUUAUGUGAUUUAGUCCACUUCCCAAGGAAAUAAUGGAAGUAUCACUUGACCUUUGAUUUUACUCUGUUGUUCCUGAAGUUAAUUUAUUCUAGAACAAUGACUCCUUAUUCACAUAGUAGCUUGAUUUCUACCUGAGUAAUAAAACUUCACUAAAUUAGAUCAGAGUAGAUAGUGGGGCCAAAGGAAUGUUUAAAUUGUCAACCAUGUAAAGAAGUUUAGUACGUCCAUCUGAGGCCCUAGUUCAGGCGCUCUUUCCAGCUGCAGUGUUUCAUUGUCCAGCGACAUUGUGGUGGCUGUCCUUGCUGUUGAAUCUCAGGAGCAUAUUAAUGAAAAGUGCCAUAAACUGAAAAACCAAACAUGAGGGUAGCAGGUGCUGCAAAGUUGGUGGUAGCUGUGGCAGUGUUUUUACUGACAUUUUAUGUUAUUUCUCAAGUAUUUGAAAUAAAAAUGGAUGCAAGUUUAGGAAAUCUAUUUGCAAGAUCAGCAUUGGACACAGCUGCACGUUCUACAAAGCCUCCCAGAUAUAAGUGUGGGAUCUCAAAAGCUUGCCCUGAGAAGCAUUUUGCUUUUAAAAUGGCAAGUGGAGCAGCCAACGUGGUGGGACCCAAAAUCUGCCUGGAAGAUAAUGUUUUAAUGAGUGGUGUUAAGAAUAAUGUUGGAAGAGGGAUCAAUGUUGCCUUGGCAAAUGGAAAAACAGGAGAAGUAUUAGACACUAAAUAUUUUGACAUGUGGGGAGGAGAUGUGGCACCAUUUAUUGAGUUUCUGAAGGCCAUACAAGAUGGAACAAUAGUUUUAAUGGGAACAUACGAUGAUGGAGCAACCAAACUCAAUGAUGAGGCACGGCGGCUCAUUGCUGAUUUGGGGAGCACAUCUAUUACUAAUCUUGGUUUUAGAGACAACUGGGUCUUCUGUGGUGGGAAGGGCAUUAAGACAAAAAGCCCUUUUGAACAGCACAUAAAGAACAAUAAGGAUACAAACAAAUAUGAAGGAUGGCCUGAAGUUGUAGAAAUGGAAGGAUGCAUCCCCCAGAAGCAAGACUAAUGGAAAUGUGGAGAGAAUUGAAGAAAGCGCACUUUCACUCUUAAUGGGAGAGCUAUAAAUGGCAGAGCUAUGUGUAAAUAUUUUAAGAGCAUGCAGCCAUCUUGGUGUGUGCAUGAGUAUUGUCUCUUUUGAUAUCAGGAUUAUUUAUUGCUAACGUAAAUAGAUAGCAUUGUAAAUAAUCAUCACAAUGAUCAAAUCACUGAACCAUGUCUCCGCACAUUUCCCUAAAAGUACAAUGUUUAGACUGCUAUGGUAAUACAUAUUUUAAAUUCUAAAAGCAUACACAAUGUGUAACUGAAUGGUUUGUGAAAAAUAUAUUGAUAUAUAUACUAGUUGCUAUGAAAAUAUCAUGGAAUAAUAGGGAUUUUAGGGUGGAUACUUUAUUUUCUUUUAUGUUUCUAUAUGUUGCGUUGUGAUGACAUUAUCUUUUAAAUUAAAAAGAGAUUUGGCUAGUUGUGUGUGUAAUGUUACUUUACAGUCCGACUCUCCUGAUGUACCUCUUUUCAUGAUCUUUUUCUUUCCUUCCCAAGAAACUGAGGAAUGUUUAAUAUGAAAACAUACAUCGGAUAUGUGAAAAGCACAACAAAAUUCUUAAUGUACACAGUAAAAAAGUAAAUAUAUAAAUGUAGAUGGCAUUUAGGACCACAGCUUGCUGGAUUUGUGUUAGCUAUGGGAAUAACUUGAUUUUGUAUAAGCUAUUUAGAGUGAGGCUGGAGGUGGCAGCUUCACAGAACUGGAGAACCAGGCCAAGUCCCCUCCCCAACCUAAUUAGGUCAUUCAGGACAGCUAAGUCAGUAUAUUUAGAGCAAUACUAGCAUACGUUUUUCUUAAUUGUUAUCAGCAUUGACCAAGUGGUUUGGAAGGAGGCAUGCUUUAAUAUCACAAUAAUUUUGAUUUGUAAACCAAGAAAUUAAUCCUGUGUUUAUCUAACUUCAUAAUAGCAAUUAUUGCCCGAAGCUAUAGUGGCAUAUUUACAAAAGUUCUUAUUACUGGGCGGACUGAUAACAUUUAAAAAAUAAUUGUGUUUGACCCCAAAUGACUUUAUACCCAAUUCUACAUAAAAAUAUAGAAGAUCUAUCUUUUUUUGUUACCUUCAGAUGUUCACUAAAUAACUCAGUUUUUAAGCAGAAGUUUUCAGGGCAUUAAAUAUAUGUUGUGUAUGAAGUAUCUCAAACUGGAACAUAAAUUUAGUGAUCAAACUGCCAUUCACAGUGUAAGGCAGCACUUAAAUUUCGAACCUAAAGUUUAGAUGCAUUGUAUAAAAAAACCUAAAAGCAGUAUCUGUUAUUUAGCUGUAAACCAAGUUGGAAGCUAUUCGGAUAAUUUCUUAAAUAUUGAUGAACUUUGGAGUACUGUUUCUUCCUUCAAACUGAAUGUAAUUAAUUCAUGAAUAAAUGCACCUUAUAUGUUUAAACAAUCUUUGUAUACUUUUGGGAUUUUUGGUGCUUAUAUGCUAAAUCACAUUCAGCAUGUGUAUUUUGACAUUUAAAAUACUUCCCUCAAUUCUGUAAAUUAAAAGAAUAGUUAUUUUACAGUUCCAGGGAUUGUGAAAUAAAUGUUGCAGUUUUUUAAAAUAAUGAAAA